AGAACCGCCUGGGUCUCUGAGGGCCUCAGGGGCAGCCUUGGUGAGUGUGGCCGACCACCGGAGGAGGAAGGACGGUCCUCCUGGGUCCUGAGUGUGUGCCUUGGUAGCUUGGCAAGCUGCCAUCUCCUUCUGACCUGGGUCACAUCCACAGUGGACACUCCCAGGACCGCACCCCCACUCUGGGUCACAGAGUACAUCUUGGGUGGGUCUGUUGUACAUAGACUGUUAGAAACGGGGCAGAGUGGCCUGAGGACGAGGUGCUCAGCAGCCUCUCUCUUCCUGCCCCUGUUGAGCCAGUGCCUGACACUGACCGCCCUUGGGGCCCUGAGCUAAGCUUCACACAGAAGCCCCUCCCCAGAUUCCUUCCCAGGUUGCAGGGCUCCCACCCGAGGUGGAGCCCCCUCUGCAGGGCAGCCUGGGGGUGUUUGUGCUGUGGGGCUUGUUGCUUCCUGCCAAGGUCAGCAGGGGGUGGCUGUGCUCUCAGGGAGAAACAGUGGCUGAGGGGCUUCGUGAUGCAUCCAGGAGAGUGCCUUAACUGUUUUCAUCCCCGUAGCUUGCUUUCUUUUUUUUUUUUUUGAGACAGAGUCUCGCUCUGUCGCCCAGGCUGGAGUGCAGUGGUGUGAUCUUGGCUCACUGCCACCUCUGCCUCCUGGGUUCAAGCAAUUCUCCUGCCUCAGCCUCCCAAAUAGCUGGGACUAUAGGCGUGUGCUACCACGCCCGGCUAAUUUUUUGUAUUUUUAGUAGAGAUGGGGUUUCACCGUGUUAACCAGGAUGGUCUCAAUCUCCUGACCUCGUGAUCCGCUCGUCUUGGCUCUCAAAGUGCUGGGAUUACAGGUGUGAGCCACCGCGCCCGGCCCAUCCCCGUAGCUUUCCCAGUGACUGUGAAUGUGGCACGAAUUUGGGCAAGGGAUACCCUCUGCCUCCAACCACCAGGCCUCAUGGGGCACCCUGGGCUGGGCCUGAAUCUCGCCUCUAAGAUGAGCCUUAGAGUUGGGGGCCAGACCUGGUCUCCCUGGUCUCCCUGGUCUCCCUGGCCCUGGGAGGAGAUGGGCUCCCAUAGUGGAGUGUUAGCUGUUUUCAGGGGAGAGGUGGAGGCAGCUGGAAAGCUUGGGUGCACUGGGGCUCGGCAGAAGGGGCCAGUCUGCUCUGUGGUGAGGCUGAGGACGGGUGGCCUUGGGAGUGUGGCAGAGAGGAGGCGCUCUAAUAGCAGUUGAGCUUGGAAGGCCCAAAAGUGAGGUGGCCCUACAGACUGACAGGUCGAAGGCACACACAUGGCCUUGUCUGCAGGGGAGUUGAGAUGGAGGCCUGGAGGGGCCUCCUGGGGAGAGGAGAGCCCAUGGGCCGCUUCUGCUGGGCUCCAAAUAGUCCCAUGGAGGUGAAUGGGGUUUGGGACCUCCUAGCUGCCUGAGCAGGAAGCACAGUGGCAAGGCAGAGCUGCAUUCUCAGGGACCCAACCCCCACAGAGGCCUGGCCUGGGCUCUGAUGAGGGGAUGGCCCAUGUCAGGCCCUAGAGCGUUCUCAUUCACCUCAGAAACGUCAGGAACCCAGGGCUAGGAGAGGCCCAUGCUGUGCCCUGGAGGACCCCAGUGACCUAGGUCAGUCCCUUAGCUUCUUCCAUUGUCAGAUGUGAUCAGAUCAUGGUCACUGUUGUCUGGGGGAAAGCAGUUGUUAUCUGGCACCGCAGACCAUGGGCAGAAGGCAGGUUUGGUGAGAGGGCAGUUUCUCGAAGGCCUUCCGUUCAAAAUUCCUAGGUCCAGUACCUGUUGUUGGUGAGUUUUAGUGAAUGAUUAAAAAGAAAAACAAAACCCCACCAAACUCUUGCACUCCUCUUGAGGAGCACAGGUGGAGGCAAAAGAGCAUUGGUUGUGAAGCCUCAUGUGCUUCCUUGCCGGUUUUGUUAUGUUUUGUUUUGUUUUGUUCUAAAGACAGUAUCUCUCUCUGUCACCCCUGCCGGAGUGCAGUGGUGGAACCAUGGCUCACUGCAGCCUCGAUCGCCUGUGCUUAGGUGAUCCUUCUGCCUCAGCACCUGAGUAGCUGGGACUGCAGGUGCGCAUUACCACACCUGGCUAAUUUUUAAAUUUUUUAUUUUUCUUUCUUGAGACUGAGUCUCACUCUGUUGCCCAGGCUGGAGUGCAGUGGUAUGAUCUUGGCUCACUGCAACCUCCCCCUCCCAGGUUCAAGCGAUUUUCUUGCCUCAGCCUCCCGGGUAGCUGGAAUUUCAGGCACCUGCCACCACGCCUGGCCAAAGUUUGUGUUUUUAGUAGAGAUGGGGGUUUCACCACGUUGGCCAGGCUGGUCUCGAACUCUUGACUUCAAGUGAUCCACCCACCUCGGCUUCCCAAAGUGCUGGGAUUACAGGCGUGAGCCACCACAGCGUCUGGCUGCCAAACGGGAUUCUGUGCCCAUCACACUGGCACUUGCAGAUUUGCUCUGUUUCAGACACUGCAGAGUGCGCUAGAGGGGACAGAGGGGCCUGACACUGUGGCCCAGGUGCCCAUGGAGUGUACUUGUGCAGCAGGUGCCCACAUACGACAGCGUCUUUCCCUGUUUGAAGAAAGGCAGAUGCAAAAGGUGGAAUAAUAAGGGGGAAAGGCAAAGUUAAGGUGUUGGCAGGAGGGCUUGUGCCAGGCAUGGGUUGCAUGGCUCUGAGAUGCACUGUCCUGGAAGCAGGCCUGGGCCAUGCCUGGAGAUUGACCCAUGGAGGUGCAGGCAGGGUGGGCAGGGCAGGCAGGGUGCUUGUCCCUCCCUUGGAGGGAGACUUCUGUCUGUCUGAUGAAGCAGGGCUCAGGGACAUAGAAGCACUGUAACUUGAAGAAUUGUGUAGUAAAUGUUUGUCAUAUCCUGCUACCCUGGGAUCAUGUGAGGUUGGAUAAGUUGUGAAAUCUUCAUGGGGACCCCAGGGCUCAGUUUUCCUGUGAGGUUGGGAUGAGGUCUGCUGUGACCUCGGGCAGCCCUGUCCUCUCUCAGUACCUCAUUUUCCUCAGUUGUAACAACCGGAACCCGAUCCCAUGCAGUUUAGGAUGAGAGUGGGUUAGUGAUGGAGGCUGGCCGUCUGUGGUACCACGAGUCCUUGCGUGUGAUUUGGCUGUGAUUUCUACGGACAGGGAGUCCAAGCAGCUCCCCCACCCCCAGCUAUGACGCAGGAAUGGACAGACAUCUGAGGGGCUUCCCAUGAGACACAGGCCACUUUCUGCUCACCUGCUGAGCGCCUUCUGGAAGAAGGACCUGGAUAGUGUCCAAAAACCCUGCACUGCAACUGCCAGGUGGGCGGUGGCAUCCGGGGAAUAUCCAGGGAGCAUCUGUGGUCAUGACCCAGGGUGCAUGCAGACAAAGGAAUCUGAGAGACCCUUCACUGGGGGCUGUGGCAGCCACGGGUGUAGGCAGGAGUUACCCAGAGCUGCUAGUUUGGGAGGGGAGAGGGGAGUUGGUAAAGAAUGGCAGUUUGGAGGAUUUUCCUAAAAUAGAGCUAUUUAAAAAAAAGAUGGGAGUGUGAUGGCUCACGCUUAUAAUCCCAGCACUUUGAGAAGUUGAGGUGAGAGGAUCGCUUGAGCCCAGGAGUUUGAGACCAGCCUGGGCAACACAGGGAGACCCCCACCUCUACAAAAGAGUUAAAAAAACAACGUAGCUGGGCAUGGUGGCACAGCUGCUUGGGGAUAAGGUGGGAGGAUUCUUGAGCCCAGGAGACUGUGGCUGCAGUGAGCUGUGAUAGUGCCACUGCCCACUGCCUGGGCAACAGAGUGAGGCCCUGUCUCAAAACAACAGCAGCAACAACAACAACAACAACAACAACAACAACAAAAACCAAAAAGAUGGGAGGAACUAAGACACAAAAUCAAGACCCACCCAUAAAAGAAAAAAAUUGAAAAAUUCCACUCCAUCAAAAUUAAGAACUUCUGUAUUUUGAGAGAUACUGUUAAGAGAAUGGAAAGGCAGUCCAGGCGCAGUGGCUCACGCCUGUAAUCCCAGCAUUUUGGGAGGCCGAAAUCACUUGAGGUCAGGAGUUUGAGAUCAGCCUGGCCAACAUGGUGAAAACCCGUCUCGACUAAAAAUACAAAAAAAUAAGCUGGGUGUGGUAGUACGCACCUGUAGUCCCAGCUACUUGGGAGGCAGAGGCAGAGGCAGAGGCAGAGGCAGGAGAAUUGCUUCAACCCAGGAGGCGGAGGUUGCAGUGAGCUGAGAUCACACCACUGCACUUCAGCCUAGGUGACAGGGCGAGACCCUGUUUAAAAAAAAAAAAAAAAAAAAAAAAAAAAGGAAUGAAAAGACAAGCCAUGGACUAGGAGUAAAAUGUAAAAUUUAUCUGAUAAAGCUCUUGUAUAUAAAAAAAAAAACCUCAAAACUUAGUAAGAAAAUGACCCAAUUUUUAAAAAUGGGAUAAAGAUUUGUACAGCUUCACCACUGAAGCUAGAAGAAUGGCACAUUAGCCUGUAAAAAGAUGCUCAACAUGCUUAAUCAGCAGGGAAACCCAAACAUGAACCUCCACGAGCUGUCACUGCACCACACACCUACCAGAAUGGCUGACAUUUUAAAUAAGCUGACAGCACUAAAUGUUGACGUGGAUGGGGAGCAACAGGAACUCUCAUUCGCUGCCGGCGGCAGUACAAAAUGGUACAGCAACUUUGGGAGCCAGCCUGGCAGUUUCAUAUUAAAUUAAAUGUACACCUACUCUGUAACCCAGCAGUCGGGCUCCUGGGUGUUCACCAAGUGAAAUGAAAACACGUCCACAGAAAAACCUGUCCAUGAGUAUUUAUAGCUGCUUGAUUCAUUAAUUCUCCAGACUGGAAACAACCUGUGUCCUUCAUCCAGCAAAUGGAUGCACGGGAAGGUGGCGUAUUUAUACUGCGGGGCAACACACAGGAUGGAUCUCAAAGGCGUCAUGCUGAGUAGGUGGUUGGCUGAAUCAUGGCCACAGCAGAUUCCAGGAACCUGUGAGUGUAACCUUCUGUGGAAAAAGGGACUUUGCAGAUGAGAUUAGGUUAAGGAUCUUGAGAUGGGGAGGUUACCCUGCAUUAUCUGGGUGGUCCCUGUUUGUCAUCACAAGUGUCCUCGUAAGAGAGGGACAGAUUUAAUGUAGACAGAAGAGGACUUGAAGGCUGCAUGACCCCAGUGGGCAGAGAUUAGGGUGAUGCAGCCACAAGCCAGGGAGUGCCUGAGCCUGCAGCAGGUGAAGAGGCCAGGAAAGGUCCUCCCCUAGAGCCCCCAAAAGGAGGGAGCCUGCUAACACUUGGAUUUCAGACUUCUGGCCCCCAGUCCGUGAGAGAACCAGUUUCCAUUGUUUUAAGCCACAAGUUUAUGCUCAGUUGUUGCAAGGACCACGGGAAACUCAUCUUAUGUGAUUCCAUUGAUAAGACUUUCUGGAAAGGCAAAACCAUAGGGACAAAAAAACAGAUCCAGGAUUGCUGAGGGUGCGGGGAGGGUCAGUCUCCAAGUGGGGAUGCAGGAAAUUGGGCAGAAAGGAAGGUGGCCUGCUCAGCGUGCUGUCCUGGGAAAAGCAAGCAAGGUGCGUGGAGCGUGUAGAGGCCACAGUUUUGGGCAAUCUGCAUAUUUUUGUCUACAAGAUUUCUGAAAAACCCUUUUCCAUAAGCUUUCUAUGCACCUUCGUGAAUGCAGAUAGAAAUAUCUGCUGCGGGCUGGGUGCGGUGGCUCACACCUGUAAUCCUGGCACUUUGGGAGGCUGAGUCUGUCGAGUUGCUUGAACCUAGGAGUUCAAGUCCAGCCUGGGCAACAUGGCAAAACCCUAUCUCUACAGAAAAUAGAAAAAUUAGCCAGGUGUGUUGGUGUGUGCCUGUGGUCCCAGCUACUCGGGAGCUGAGGCAGGAGGAUCACCUGAGCCUAGAAGGUCGAAGCUGCAGUGAGCCGUGUUCACACCACCGCACUCCAGCCUGGGUGACAGAGUGAGAGCUUAUCUCCAAAAAGAAAGAAAGAAAAAAAAUACUUGCUAUGCCGGCCACUGAAUUACACUUGGCUUGUAGCCAGUUGGAGUCCCUUUCCUGCUCUUACAGGCCCACCUGGCCUGCUGAACACACCAUCUGUCCUCCCAGGCUGGCAGAGGAGCUGCCGUGGGUCCUGCCCUCUGCUCUGCCCUGACCGUGGCCACCUGGUUCCCUAGGCUGGAACCAGUGAGGUCCACAAUGUGUCUGUCCAAGUUCCCUAGCUCGUCCCUGAGCCAACCAAGCUCACUGGGCAGAUCUUCCUUUGUUUUGUAGUUCACGGAGACAGCCCCACUCAGUCACUGUCUAAACUCUCCGUGGCCUCAAUGUCCUGCUCCAGUCCUGCCAGGAAGUCUCAAGGAGGAUUCCUGAAUAGCGUUUCCCAAUCAUUUGUGCUUUACUGGAAAGGGGGGGCCUGUUGUGGGGAGGCCACCGUCCAGGGCUCUUCCCGGGACUUCACCUUCCCUCUGCUGGACCACACGCCGUGGCUUGGCAGGGUGACCCAGCUCUGUAAGAUCAGGACGUGUGUGCUGACACUGGUGCUUGGGAGAGUCAGCAAGAUGGACUUCUGAAGAAGGAACAGAUGCAUUCCUUUCUGUCAUUUCCUGCAUCAGGGGUGGGGUGGCAGGCCUUGCCCAGUAGACAGCAGGGAGAACGUGCUGCCUGGGGAGAGUGGGCACUUCUGCUGAGUGGGUGCUUCUGGAGGGUGGUGGGAAGGAUCAUGUGUCUUUGGGGCAGCCUUGGCACCUGCUGCCUUGGGCCUCAUUGUCCCCAGGCUGGUAGCAGGUAUCCUGGGACCUGGCCAGAUUGGGCCCCGUCCAUCUGUCUGUGUGUCUCAUCUCUUCACUGUGCCCUCUCCCUAGUUUCUGUCUUUGCUGGAGAGUUUUUAAAACAAUCCUAGAUUUUUUUUUUUUUUUUUUUUUGAGAUGGAGUCUCACUCUGUCGUGCAGGCUGGAGUGCAGUGGCUUGAUCUCAGCUCACUGCAACCUCCGCCUACCGGGUUCAAGCAGUUCUCCUGCCUCAGGCUCCCGAGUAGCUAGGAUUAUAGGCGUAUGCCACCAUGCCUGGCUAAUUUUUGUAUUUUUAGUAGAGAUGGAGUUUCACCAUGUUGGUCAGGCUGGUCUUGAACUCCUGACCUCAAGCAGUCCACCUGCCUCAGCCUCCCAAAAUGCUGGGAUUACAGGUGUGAGGUACCAUGCCUGGCCAACAAUCAGAUACGUUCUUCUUCACCCGUAACUUUUCCAUUUAUAUUUUAUAUUUGUUGAAGGGAGCAGGUCUUUUUUCCCAUAGAUUUUUCUGCUUUCUGCUCUGAUGGUCGCUUCCCGUGGCAGGGUCAGCCCAGGGCUUCUCAGCCCCUGCACUGCUUGACAUUUGGGGCAGGAGGUUCUGUGUUGCCUGCAGUGUGCUGAGCAGCAUCCCUGGCCUCCCCCGAGCCAGAUGGUGGGGACUGUCCCCGCCCUCAGUGGUGAGGACCAGAAAUGGCUCCAGACAUUGCCUCGUGCCCUGGGGAAGAUUCACCCACCACACUUCCUGUAAACUGGUCACUCGGCCUGGAGGUGGAUUUCGUAAGCCACUUCCUGUUGCUUCAUCCCCGGAAGUGCUCUUUGCCGGAGGGGAGAGGAUCAGGGGAUUCUGGCCCUGGAGAGGUUCCUCCUCACCCUUUCCUCUGUCUCAGCAUUGAGGACUCUCACUGCCUCCCAGGCUCUGCACCCUCGACCCUUUUCCCAAAGGCAUUGCUGUCUUUACAGGAGUGUCCUCAUUGAGGGGGAGCUGCCUACAGGAGUCUCCCAGUCUGUGUUCAGUAGCCCCAGUGGGCGCCCAGGCCAAGUGACCGCAGGGCGCAGGCAUCACUGCCCUGCUGUGUUGAGGUCUGUUCUCCGAGUCAGGGUCUGAAGUCCAGUUGGGUCUGGGGAGCACCAGCCUCGGCACAGCUCAGUGCCUGCCUGUCCGGCCUUGAAGACCCAGCUGACCUGCUGACUGUGUCAGGCCAGCUGUGGCGGCCCUACCAGGCUCCCCAGCUCCCACCUGGGGCCCUGGCCUGAAGUACAGCAGCGGGGGUGACUUUGUAUCUCAGGAGCUCCCAGUUCCAUACCUCAUGCUGGGUAAUGAAAGUUGGAUUUUUGCCACUCGAGGGCCUGAGAGGACUUGUGGGGGUGAUGACCCCUCAGAGGGUCUACAGAGACUGGGCAGGCGGUGGCCUGAGGCAUGGCUCUCCCCUGCUGGGUGUUCUUGGGUGUGAGAUGGGCAGUACCCUGCAGGUGUCAUGUGCUACUGAGUUACCCCGUUAUUUAAUUAAUGCAGCCUGAGGCCAACCCCAAAGCUUCUAAGGCAGCAGGGAAAUCACCUGUGCUACAGUCUGUUCCUGACCCUCUGUCCUGCUUCAUAGAUGAGGUAACGAGGCGCUUGGCCCCCCUGACAAGGGUUCGGCCAUGACACCACGCAUGUUGGCUCUGGAGGGAGCAGCCAGAAGAGGGUGUGGUGGGCCACAUGCUGUCAGGCGUCCCCACCAGGCCAGGCUGGUGAGCACAGAGGGUGACAGCUGGUCCCACCGUGAAGGGACCUAGCUGGCUCUGCCUGUCUGCAGCCGACACUCACCUCCUGGGCCCUUGAUUGGCUUGUCAGGGCACUGCACCCCAGCUGCUUUCUGUGUUUUUUCUCAUCCCCCCCACCCAGUCCUUGUGUUCUCAUCACCAUCUAUUUAGCACCCCACAUUCAAAACCCCAGCCUCACUACCGUAAUUUAUGCCUUGAAUGAUCUUUUGCAGAAACAUCAUAAGAAAAAAGCCUUUUCUAUUCAUGCAUGCUCACUGUGCCCGCGUCAUCCUCUGCAAAUCCAUAGGUCCAUUUAGGGUCACUCUCCCUCCUUCUGAAGAACUUCUAGAACCUUCCUCACAGUGCAGGCCAGAUGCUGACAGAAGAUUCUCUCAGCAUUUGUUUGAGCGAAUCUUUAUUUCCCUUUCUCUUUUCACUGGGCAUGGAAUUGUGGUCUGGCGGUGUUUCUCCCUCAGCACUUUGAAGAUGCCCUCCCAGUGUCGGGGCUGGCUCCUGAUGUGCAGUGUCGGCACCUCGGCACUUGGGGCGACUGUUGUGGCUGUGCUGAUUUGCUCAUGAUGCGCCACGACCUGGUAGUUUUCCUGCUGGGGGUUGACAAGGCUUCUUGGGUCUGUGGAUUUAUAGCAUUUGUUACAUUUGGGAAUCUCUGGCCACUCUUUUCUCAGAUCCCCCGCCUGCCCUCAGGACUCCAGUUACUUGCACGUGGGAUCCCCUGCUGUCGUCCGCAGGUCACCGAGGUGGUGUUCGUUUCCUGUAGGCUUCUUACUGUGGGAUUCAUCUAGGUGGCUCCUGUGGCUUUGUCUUCAAGUUCGCUGCCCUUUUCUUCUGUGGUGCCUGCUGUGACUUCCACCUAGUGGCCGUUUCAUUCCGAUCCUCCGUGUCUCAGCUCCAGAAGCCCCUCGUGGCUCUCUCACGAUACCCAACUCGCCGUGUGUGUGUCAGAGAAUGUUGCUCCUGUGCCCUGAGUCAACAAAGACGGCCCCUGUGAGCUCAAGGGCAGUUGGGAAGGUGUAGCGAACAUCCUGUAAAACGUCCCAUCUUGAUUCUGUUUCACUGAGGCCAUCUAUCCGAUUUCAAGGAAGCCAAGGGCACAUCUCCAUCCCCCAGCCUGACUGCCCCGCAGAGGCGCGGACGUUCUCCUUCUACCUCUCCAACAUCGGCCGCGACAACCCCCAGGGCAGCUUCGACUGCAUCCAGCAGUAUGUCUCCAGUCAUGGGGAAGUUCACCUGGACUGCCUGGGCAGCAUACAGGACAAGAUCACGGUGUGUGCCACCGACGACUCCUACCAGAAGGCGCGGCAGAGCAUGGCCCAGGCGGAGGAGGAGACGCGGAGCCGAAGUGCCAUUGUCAUCAAGGCUGGAGGCCGCUACCUGGGCAAGAAGGUUCAGUUUCGGAAACCAGCCCCAGGUGCAACAGACGCGGUGCCCUCCCGGAAGCGGGCAACCCCCAUCAACUUGGCGAGUGCCAUCAGGAAGAGUGGUGCCAGUGCCGUGAGUGGGGGCAGCGGGGUGUCCCAGAGGCCCUUCCGUGACCGAGUGCUGCACCUCCUGGCACUACGGCCCUACCGCAAGGCUGAGCUGCUGCUGCGACUGCAGAAGGACGGCCUGACGCAGGCGGACAAGGACGCGCUGGAUGGCCUCCUCCAGCAGGUGGCCAACAUGAGUGCUAAGGACGGCACGUGUACACUGCAGGACUGCAUGUACAAGGAUGUGCAGAAGGACUGGCCUGGCUACUCGGAGGGGGACCAGCAGCUGCUGAAGCGGGUGCUCGUCCGGAAGCUGUGCCAGCCACAGAGCACUGGCAGCCUCCUUGGAGACCCUGCUGCCUCCAGCCCCCCAGGCGAGCGUGGGCGCUCGGCCUCGCCCCCACAGAAGCGGCUGCAGCCUCCUGAUUUCAUCGACCCCCUAGCCAACAAGAAACCCCGGAUAUCGCACUUCACUCAGAGAGCUCAGCCUGCCGUCAACGGGAAGCUGGGCGUGCCCAAUGGCCGUGAGGCCUUGCUGCCCACCCCGGGCCCACCAGCCAGCACGGACACCCUCAGCUCCAGCACUCACCUGCCCCCGCGGCUGGAGCCCCCGAGGGCCCACGACCCCCUGGCCGAUGUCAGCAAUGACCUGGGCCACAGCGGCCGAGACUGUGAGCACGGAGAGGCGGCUGCCCCAGCCCCCACUGUGCGCCUCGGCCUGCCCCUGCUGACGGACUGUGCCCAGCCCAGCAGGCCACACGGCAGCCCCUCGCGCAGCAAGCCCAAGAAGAAGUCCAAGAAGCACAAAGACAAGGAGAGGGCGGCUGAGGACAAGCCCCGGGCCCAGCUUCCAGACUGUGCACCUGCCACCCAUGCCACCCCCGGAGCCCCAGCAGACACCCCAGGUUUAAACGGAACCUGCAGCGUUUCCAGUGUUCCCACGUCCACGUCGGAGACGCCUGACUACUUGCUGAAGUACGCAGCCAUCUCCUCUUCGGAGCAGCGCCAGAGCUACAAGAACGACUUCAAUGCCGAGUACAGCGAGUACCGCGACCUGCACGCCCGCAUUGAGCGCAUCACGCGGCGGUUCACCCAGCUCGACGCCCAGCUCCGGCAGCUCUCCCAGGGCUCCGAGGAGUAUGAGACUACUCGAGGGCAGAUUUUGCAGGAAUAUCGAAAAAUCAAAAAGACCAACACCAACUACAGCCAGGAGAAGCACCGCUGCGAGUACCUGCACAGCAAGCUGGCCCACAUCAAGAGGCUCAUCGCCGAGUACGACCAGCGGCAGCUGCAGGCUUGGCCCUAGCCGCCCUCCCCGAUGGCGGGGAUCUGGGAGGGUCGGGGGAGCAAAAGGCGGUGAGAGAGGAUUUAUUUAAAAAAAUAAACCCGAGGAAGAUGCUCAUCUGAGCCAGCACCGCCGGCUUUCAGGGCAGCCCCUGCAGACGUCUGGCCCUGGCGGGUGGCUGCAAGCCCACCUCGGCCCUCCCUGCGCUUCCUGAGCAGUCCCUGCUUAUGAUGGGCUCCCCAGGAAGCCCACUGCCUCCUCCCUGGCUGCAGCCUCCGGGGUUCAGCCUCCUGUCUCGCCAGAAGACUCCUAGGCCCUUGGGGUGGCGCGCCUGCCUUUUCUAGUUUUAUACAAAGACAGCCACUUUUAGCUACUGCUAAUGAGACUUGAGUCUAUUUUUGUACAAAAGAGAAGCAAAAUCUUUUUUCUAAACCUGUGCCUCCCUCUCCUCGGACACCCAGGGUCUAGCCGCUGCCCUGGGUCCUGCCUGCAGUAUUACAGAGGUCGUCGAAAGGUGCAGCUGCGUUCUGAGGGCGUGGGGAAUGGGCAGGUGGCCUCUGCUGGUCUCUGGCUCUACGUUUAGGCACCCCUUUCCCCAGCCUCUCCUCCUUGGGCAGGGUCUCUGCUCCAGCAAGCAAACAGGGUGGCCCAGGUGGCUAUUUUGAGAACUCCAGCUGGUGCCCCCAGACAGCUGCUCAGAGCCAAGGGGGCAGAGGGCUUUCAGCGCCCCCAGGCCUGCCCUGCUAUUUCAGGCCCUCAGCUGUCGGGGGCCACUGUGUUUCUGUGCUCCAAGUUGAGACUCGGCCGCAGCGGCGUCAGACUUUUCUUUGCGAUGUCCUCGGUUUCCCAUUUGUUGCUGCUGCUGCUCAUUCCACACUGUUGAGACCUUGUGGUCUCGAUGCUGCUGGCCUCCCUCCGUCCCUCUGUCCACUUGUGGGUCCUGGGGUCGUCUUAGCAGAGCCACCGCCAAGGUUUGCACUCAGGGAGGGGCUGAUGGAGGGCUGGGCGCCAUGGGGUCAGGGAGGCCCCAGGGACCCAUGGGCAGAGCUGGGGAGCCAGGAGGAUGGGUCUGCCUGCUCUGGGGGUGCAGGCUCUGCAGACACCCCAAUUGCUGCUCUGUUGCUGUGCCUAGUCUAGUGUCCCCCAAAGCAUCGGGGGGCCACGCAAGUGUGGGUGUGUGAGUGUGCGUAUGUGGGGACCCCCCAGGGCAUGGUGGGGUCUGAGGCGUGUGUUCCCAUUUAGGGCUGAAUGAAGCCAUGACUUGGAAAGGUGGUGGGGGGUGGAUGGCGGCUGUGACUCAGGGCCCAGGGAUCACAUGGGGGUCACUGCUGCCAUCAGCAGUCAGGCAGGGAGAACAGAAAUGCAAAAAUACAGAUGUCUAUUUUUCUAAACUGGGGGGUGGAGGGGUGCCUCCUGACAGCUUCCAAAGAGCUGACUGUGGAGGGCCCACAGUGUAUCCCACCCCUGCCCGAGAGUCUCUCUCCUUUGGGACCCCCGGGUUCCCAGAGCUCCGAGGAAACUGAUCCUUCAUGUUUCAAUAGCUGUUGUUGUUUUUCUCUUUGGGCCGGGCCGGGCCGGGGAAGGGCCGAGCAGGCUCCAGGAGGCCUCCAGAGUCAGCUGGACCUUGCUGUGUCGCCCGCAGGCAGCCCUGCAGACACCGGUGAGGUGGGAUGAUUUCAGGAGGUCCCAGCCCGGGACUGCCCGCCCCUCUGCCCUGGGAACCAGUCCAAGGGGCUGUCAGUUGAAUUUGCCUUUUUGUUGUUGUUGUUGUUUUUGUUGUUUAUUUGUUCUCCUUUUAAGGAAUUAUGAAGCUAAGAAAAGUUUUGUGUUUUGGGGGUUGGUGGACAAAGUUCUAGCUGAUUAAAUAUGGUCUAACUUAUUGAUACUAUUUUUUUUUCUUUUAAUGUUGUACUGUGGAGAAAAACUAUUUUGAGCCAUGGGGUUGGUGUUUACAAGAACUUUCCACUUUUGCCAAAAUGUUACAAUUGAAAGGCAUCUAUCUGCGUCUUCAGUUUCCUGAUAUUUUCUUAAAAGAUCUAGUGUCCUUUUUGUACACUAAACAGGUGAAUGCUGACUUUUUUCAUUCUCCAAUAAAUUUCACUGAACUGAA